AGCCUGCCUGACCGCGCGGAGGAGGAGGGCGGGCGCGGUGCCGCCGGGGCGGGAAGGUCGCGGGCGGCUGCUCCGGACUGCAGCUCCCGCGGCGGUGGCGGCGUAUCGGGACACGGCGCGGGAUGGACGCGCAGGACUGCCAGGCGGCCGCAUCGCCCGAGCCGCCCGGGCCCCCAGCCCGUAGCUGCGUGGCCGCCUGGUGGGACAUGGUCGACCGCAACCUGCGAUAUUUUCCACACUCCUGUUCAAUGCUCGGAAGAAAAAUUGCUGCUCUGUAUGACAGCUUUACUAGUAAAUCCUUAAAAGAACACGUUUUCCUUCCUCUGAUAGACAUGCUAAUUUAUUUUAAUUUUUUCAAAGCCCCAUUUCUUGUGGAUUUAAAGAAACCAGAGUUAAAGAUUCCUCACACAGUGAACUUCUACCUGAGAGUUGAACCUGGGGUGAUGCUAGGGAUCUGGCACACAGUCCCCAGCUGCCGGGGGGAAGAUGCCAAGGGGAAGGACUGUUGCUGGUAUGAAGCAGCCCUUCGUGAUGGGAACCCAAUUAUUGUUUAUCUUCAUGGCAGUGCAGAACACAGGGCAGCUUCGCACAGACUGAAGCUGGUAAAGGUGCUGAGUGAUGGUGGCUUUCAUGUCUUGUCUGUUGACUACAGAGGAUUUGGGGACUCUACAGGUAAGCCCACAGAGGAGGGACUGACUACGGAUGCCAUUUGUGUCUAUGAGUGGACCAAGGCAAGAAGUGGCAUCACUCCCGUGUGUCUCUGGGGCCACUCUCUGGGUACAGGAGUUGCAACAAAUGCUGCAAAAGUGCUAGAAGAAAAAGGAUGCCCAGUUGAUGCUAUUGUCUUGGAAGCUCCAUUUACCAACAUGUGGGUUGCAAGUAUCAAUUAUCCCUUGUUAAAGGUAUCUGCCCAGAUGGCCUGAAGUAACUGAAGAAUCACAAAAGAAGUGAAUAUGCCCUGCCCCACCUUAACUGAUGACAUUCCACCACAAAAGAAGUAUAAAUGGCCGGUCCUUGCCUUAAGUGAUGACACUACCUUGUGAAAGUCCUUUUCCUGGCUCAUCCUGGCUCAGAAGCUCCCCCACUGAGCACCUUGUGACCCCCACCCCUGCCCACCAGAGAACAACCCCCUUUGACUGUAAUUUUCCAUUACCUUCCCAAAUCCUAUAAAACAGCCCCACCCCUAUCUCCCUUGGCUGACUCUCUUUUCGGACUCAGCCCACCUGCACCCAGGUGAAAUAAACAGCCAUGUUGCUCACACAAAGCCUGUUUGGUGGUCUCUUCACACGGACGCGCAUGAAAUUUGGUGCCGUGACUCGGAUCGGGGGACCUCCCUUGGGAGAUCAAUCCCCCAUCCUCCUGCUCUUUGCUCCAUGAGAAAAAUCCACCUAUGACCUUAGGUCCUCAGACCGACCAGCCCAAGAAACAUCUCACCAAUUUCAAAUCCGGUAAGCGGCCUCUUUUUACUCUCUUCUCCAACCUCCCUCACUAUCCCUCAACCUCUUUCUCCUUUCAAUCUUGGCACCACACUUCAAUCUCUCCCUUCUCUUAAUUUCAAUUCCUUUCAUUUUCUGGUAGAGACAAAGGAGACACGUUUUAUCCGUGGACCCAAAACUCCGGCGCUGGCCACAGACUGGGAAGGCAGCCUUCCCUUGGUGUUUAAUCAUUGCAGGGACACCUCUCUGAUUAUUCACUCACGUUUCAAGGGUGUCAGACCACGCAGGGACGCCUGCCUUGGUCCUUCACCCUUAGCGGCAAGUCCCGCUUUUCUGGGGAAGGGGCAAGUACCCCAACCCCUUCUCUCCUUGUCUCUACCCCUUCUCUGCUCUUCUGGGGGAGGGGCAAGUACCCCUCAACCCCUUCUCCUUCAUCCUUAGUGGCAAGUCCCGCUUUCCUGGGGCAGGGGCAAGUACCCCUCAACCCCUUCUCCUUCACCCUUAGCGGCAAGUCCCGCUUUCCUAGGGGGCAAAAAACCCCCAAUCGCUUAUUUCUGCACCCUGACCUCUUAUCUCUGUGCCCUAAUCCCUUAUUUCCGUGCCCCAACCCCUUCUCUGCUUUUCUGGAGGGCAAGAACCCCCCCACCCCUUCUCCAUGUCUCUACUCUUUUCUCUGGGCUUGCCUCCUUCACUAUGGGCAAGCUUCCACCUUCCAUUCCUCCUUCUUCUCCCUUAGCCUGUGUUCUCAAAAACUUAAAACCUCUUCAACUCACACCUGACCUAAAAUCUAAAUGACUUAUUUUCUUCUGCAAUGCCGCUUGACCCCAAUACAAACCGACAGUAGUUCCAAAUAGCCAGAAAAUGGCACUUUGAAUUUUUCCAUCCUGCAAGAUCUAAAUAAUUCUUGUUGUAAAAUAGGCAAACGGUCUGAGGUGCCUGACGUCCAGGCAUUCUUUUACACAUCAGUCCCUUCCUAGUCUCUGUGCCCAGUGCAACUCGUCCCAAAUCUUCCUUCUUUCCCUCCCGCCUGUCCCCCCAGUCCCAACCCCAAGCGUCGCUGAGUCUUUCUAAUCUUCCUUUUCUACAGACCCGUCUGACCUCUCCCCUCCUCGCCAGGCCGAGCUAGGCCUCAAUUCUUCCUCAGCCUCUGCUCCUCCACCCUAUAAUCUUUUUAUCGCCUCCCCUCCUCACACCUGGUCCUGCUUACAGUUUCGUUCCGUGACUAGCCCUCCCCCACCUGCCCAGCAAUUUACUCUUAAAAAGGUGGCUGGAGCUAAAGGCAUAGUCAAGGUUAAUGCUCCUUUUUCUUUAUCCCAAAUCAGAUAGCAUUUAGGCUCUUUUUCAUCAAAUAUAAAAAUCCAGCCCAGUUCAUGACGUGUUUGGCAGCAACCCUGAGACACUUUACAGCCCUAGACCCUAAAAGGUCAAAAGGCCAUCUUAUUCUCAAAAUACAUUUUAUUAGCCAAUCUGCUCCCGACAUUAAAUAAAACUCCAAAAAUUAGAUUCCGGCCCUCAAACCCCACAACAGGAUUUAAUUAACCUCGCCUUCAAGGUGUACAAUAAUAGAAAAAAGUUGCAAUUCCUUGCCUCCACUGUGAGACAAACCCCAGCCACAUCUCCAGCACACAAGAACUUCCAAACGCCUGAACCGCAGCAGCCAGGCGUUCCUCCAGAACCUCCUCCCACAGGAGCUUGCUACACGUGCCGGAAAUCUGGCCACUGGGCCAAGGAAUGCCCGCAGCCCGGGAUUCCUCCUAAGCCGCGUCCCAUCUCUCUGGGACCCCACUGAAAAUCGGACUGUUCAACUCACCUGGCAGCCACUCCCAGAGCCCCUGGAACUCUGGCCCAAGGCUCUCUGACUGACUCCUUCCCAGAUCUUCUCGGCUUAGCGGCUGAAGACUGACACUGCCCGAUCGCCUCGGAAGCCCCCUAGACCAUCACAGACGCCGAGCUUCCGGUAACUCUCACAGUGCAAGGUAGGCCCGUCCCCUUCUUAAUCAAUACGGAGGCUACUCACUCCCCAUUACCUUCUUUUCAAGGGCCUGUUUCCCUUGCCUCCAUAACUGUUGUGGGUAUUGACGGUCAGGCUUCUAAACCUCUUAAAACUCCCCAACUCUGGUGCCAACUUAGACAAUACUCUUUUAAGCACUCCUUUUUAGUUAUCCCCACCUGCCCAGUUCCCGUAUUAGGCUGAGACACUUUAACUAAAUUAUCUGCUUCCCUGACUAUUCCUGGACUACAGCUAUAUCUCAUUGCCGCCCUUCUUCCCAAUCCAAAGCCUCCUUUGCGUCCUCCUCUUGUAUCCCCCGACCUUAACCCACAAGUAUAAGAUACCUCUACUCCCUCCUUGGUGACCGAUCAUGCACCCCUUACCAUCUCAUUAAAACCUAAUCACCCUUACCCCACUCAACGCCAAUAUCCCGUCCUGCAGCAUGCUUUAAAAAGAUUAAAGCCUGUUAUCACUCACCUGCUACAGCAUGGCCUUUUAAAGCCUAUAAACUCUCCUUACAAUUCCCCCGUUUUACCUGUCAGCCCUGAGAAACAUCGCCCAUUCUCCCUCCAUACCACCCCCCAAAAAUUUUCACCGCUCCAACACUUCAACACUAUUUUGUUUUAUUUUUCUUAUUAAUAUAAGAAGGCAGGAAUGUCAGGCCUCUGAGCCCAAGCCAAGCCAUCGCAUCCCCUGUGACUUGCACAUAUACGCCCAGAUGGCCUGAAGUAACUGAAGAAUCACAAAAGAAGUGAAAAGGCCCUGCCCUGCCUUAACUGAUGACAUUCCACCAUUGUGAUUUGUUCCUGCCCCACCUUAACUGAGUGAUUAACCCUGUGAAUUUCCUUCUCCUGGCUCAGAAGCUGCCCCACCUUAACUGAGUGAUUAACCCUGCGAAUUUCCUUCUCCUGGCUCAGAAGCUCCCCCACUGAGCACCUUGUGACCCCCGCCCCUGCCCACCAGAGAGCAACCCCCUUUGACUGUAAUUUUCCAUUACCUUCCCAAAUCCUAUAAAACGGCCCCACCCCUAUCUCCCUUGGCUGACUCUCUUUGCGGACUCAGCCCGCCUGCACCCAGGUGAAAUAAACAGCCAUGUUGCUCACA